CUCUUCCGCCGUCGUCGCCGCCAUCCUCGGCGCGACUCGCUUCUUUCGGUUCUACCUGGGAGAAUCCACCGCCAUCCGCCACCAUGGUGAACUUCACGGUAGACCAGAUCCGCGCCAUCAUGGACAAGAAGGCCAACAUCCGCAACAUGUCUGUCAUCGCCCACGUGGACCAUGGCAAGUCCACGCUGACAGACUCCCUGGUGUGCAAGGCGGGCAUCAUCGCCUCGGCCCGGGCCGGGGAGACACGCUUCACUGAUACCCGGAAGGACGAGCAGGAGCGUUGCAUCACCAUCAAGUCAACUGCCAUCUCCCUCUUCUACGAGCUCUCGGAGAAUGACUUGAACUUCAUCAAGCAGAGCAAGGACGGUGCCGGCUUCCUCAUCAACCUCAUUGACUCCCCCGGGCAUGUCGACUUCUCCUCGGAGGUGACUGCUGCCCUCCGAGUCACCGAUGGCGCAUUGGUGGUGGUGGACUGCGUGUCAGGCGUGUGCGUGCAGACGGAGACAGUGCUGCGGCAGGCCAUUGCCGAGCGCAUCAAGCCUGUGCUGAUGAUGAACAAGAUGGACCGCGCCCUGCUGGAGCUGCAGCUGGAGCCCGAGGAGCUCUACCAGACUUUCCAGCGCAUCGUGGAGAACGUGAACGUCAUCAUCUCCACCUACGGCGAGGGCGAGAGCGGCCCCAUGGGCAACAUCAUGAUCGAUCCUGUCCUCGGUACCGUGGGCUUUGGGUCUGGCCUCCACGGGUGGGCCUUCACCCUGAAGCAGUUUGCCGAGAUGUAUGUGGCCAAGUUCGCCGCCAAGGGGGAGGGCCAGUUGGGGCCUGCCGAGCGGGCCAAGAAAGUAGAGGACAUGAUGAAGAAGCUGUGGGGUGACAGGUACUUUGACCCAGCCAACGGCAAGUUCAGCAAGUCAGCCACCAGCCCCGAAGGGAAGAAGCUGCCACGCACCUUCUGCCAGCUGAUCCUGGACCCCAUCUUCAAGGUGUUUGAUGCGAUCAUGAAUUUCAAGAAAGAGGAGACAGCAAAACUGAUAGAGAAACUGGACAUCAAACUGGACAGCGAGGACAAGGACAAAGAAGGCAAACCCCUGCUGAAGGCUGUGAUGCGCCGCUGGCUGCCUGCCGGAGACGCCUUGUUGCAGAUGAUCACCAUCCACCUGCCCUCCCCUGUGACGGCCCAGAAGUACCGCUGCGAGCUCCUGUACGAGGGGCCCCCGGACGACGAGGCUGCCAUGGGCAUUAAAAGCUGUGACCCCAAAGGCCCUCUUAUGAUGUAUAUUUCCAAAAUGGUGCCAACCUCCGACAAAGGUCGGUUCUACGCCUUUGGACGAGUCUUCUCGGGGCUGGUCUCCACUGGCCUGAAGGUCAGGAUCAUGGGGCCCAACUAUACCCCUGGGAAGAAGGAGGACCUCUACCUGAAGCCAAUCCAGAGAACAAUCUUGAUGAUGGGCCGCUACGUGGAGCCCAUCGAGGAUGUGCCUUGUGGGAACAUUGUGGGCCUCGUGGGCGUGGACCAGUUCCUGGUGAAGACGGGCACCAUCACCACCUUCGAGCACGCGCACAACAUGCGGGUGAUGAAGUUCAGCGUCAGCCCUGUUGUCAGAGUGGCCGUGGAGGCCAAGAACCCGGCUGACCUGCCCAAGCUGGUGGAGGGGCUGAAGCGGCUGGCCAAGUCCGACCCCAUGGUGCAGUGCAUCAUCGAGGAGUCGGGAGAGCAUAUCAUCGCGGGCGCCGGCGAGCUGCACCUGGAGAUCUGCCUGAAGGACCUGGAGGAGGACCACGCCUGCAUCCCCAUCAAGAAAUCUGACCCGGUCGUCUCGUACCGCGAGACGGUCAGUGAAGAGUCGAACGUGCUCUGCCUCUCCAAGUCCCCCAACAAGCACAACCGGCUGUACAUGAAGGCGCGGCCCUUCCCCGACGGCCUGGCCGAGGACAUCGAUAAAGGCGAGGUGUCCGCCCGUCAGGAGCUCAAGCAGCGGGCGCGCUACCUGGCCGAGAAGUACGAGUGGGACGUGGCUGAGGCCCGCAAGAUCUGGUGCUUUGGGCCCGACGGCACCGGCCCCAACAUCCUCACCGACAUCACCAAGGGUGUGCAGUACCUCAACGAGAUCAAGGACAGUGUGGUGGCCGGCUUCCAGUGGGCCACCAAGGAGGGCGCACUGUGUGAGGAGAACAUGCGGGGUGUGCGCUUCGACGUCCACGACGUCACCCUGCACGCCGACGCCAUCCACCGCGGAGGGGGCCAGAUCAUCCCCACAGCACGGCGCUGCCUCUAUGCCAGUGUGCUGACCGCCCAGCCACGCCUCAUGGAGCCCAUCUACCUUGUGGAGAUCCAGUGUCCAGAGCAGGUGGUCGGUGGCAUCUACGGGGUUUUGAACAGGAAGCGGGGCCACGUGUUCGAGGAGUCCCAGGUGGCCGGCACCCCCAUGUUUGUGGUCAAGGCCUAUCUGCCCGUCAACGAGUCCUUUGGCUUCACCGCUGACCUGAGGUCCAACACGGGCGGCCAGGCGUUCCCCCAGUGUGUGUUUGACCACUGGCAGAUCCUGCCCGGAGACCCCUUCGACAACAGCAGCCGCCCCAGCCAGGUGGUGGCGGAGACCCGCAAGCGCAAGGGCCUGAAAGAAGGCAUCCCUGCCCUGGACAACUUCCUGGACAAAUUGUAGGCGGCCCUUCCUGCAGCGCCUGCCGCCCCGGGGACUCGCAGCACCCACAGCACCACGUCCUCGAAUUCUCAGACGACACCUGGAGACUGUCCCGACACAGCGACGCUCCCCUGAGAGGUUUCUGGGGCCCGCUGCGUGCCAUCACUCAACCAUAACACUUGAUGCCGUUUCUUUCAAUAUUUAUUUCCAGAGUCCGGAGGCAGCAGACACGCCCUCUUAGUAGGGACUUAAUGGGCCGGUCGGGGAGGGGGAGGCGGGAUGGGACACCCAACACUUUUUCCAUUUCUUCAGAGGGAAACUCAGAUGUCCAAACUAAUUUUAACAAACGCAUUAAGAGGUUUAUUUGGGUACAUGGCCCGCAGUGGCUUUUGCCCCAGAAAGGGGAAAGGAACACGCGGGUAGAUGAUUUCUAGCAGGCAGGAAGUCCUGUGCGGUGUCACCAUGAGCACCUCCAGCUGUACUAGUGCCAUUGGAAUAAUAAAUUUGAUAAGGUGGUGA